GUCUUGGAGAAGCAAGAUGGCGGCGACGGCGGCCGCAGUGGUGGCCGAGGAGGACACGGAGCUGCGGGACCUGCUGGUGCAGACGCUGGAGAACAGCGGGGUCCUGAACCGCAUCAAGGCUGAACUCCGAGCAGCUGUGUUUUUAGCACUAGAGGAGCAAGAAAAAGUAGAGAACAAAACUCCUUUAGUUAAUGAGAGCCUGAAAAAGUUUUUAAAUACCAAAGACGGUCGUUUAGUGGCUAGUCUUGUUGCAGAAUUUCUUCAGUUUUUUAACCUUGACUUUACUUUGGCUGUUUUUCAACCUGAAACUAGCACACUGCAAGGUCUCGAAGGUCGAGAGAAUUUAGCCCGAGAUUUAGGUAUAAUUGAAGCAGAAGGUACUGUGGGUGGACCCUUAUUAUUAGAAGUGAUCAGGCGCUGUCAACAGAAAGAAAAAGGGCCAACCACUGGGGAAGGUGCACUUGAUCUAUCUGAUGUACAUUCUCCACCAAAGUCACCAGAGGGAAAAACAAGUGCACAGACAACACCAAGUAAGAUACCAAGGUAUAAAGGACAAGGUAAGAAGAAGACAAGCGGGCAGAAGGCUGGUGACAAGAAGGCCAAUGAUGAGGCCAAUCAGAGUGAUACAAGUGUCUCCUUGUCAGAACCCAAGAGCAAAAGCAGCCUUCACUUACUGUCCCAUGAAACAAAAAUUGGAUCUUUUCUAAGCAACAGAACUUUAGAUGGCAAAGACAAAGCUGGCCUUUGUCCAGAUGAAGAUGAUAUGGAAGGAGAUUCUUUCUUUGAUGAUCCCAUUCCUAAGCCAGAGAAAACUUACGGUUUGAGGAAGGAACCUAGGAAGCAAGCAGGAAGUCUGGCCUCGCUCUCGGAUGCACCCCCCUUAAAAAGUGGACUCAGCUCCCUGGCGGGAGCCCCUUCUUUAAAAGACUCUGAGAGUAAAAGGGGAAAUACAGUUUUGAAAGAUCUGAAAUUGAUCAGUGAUAAAAUUGGAUCACUUGGAUUAGGAACUGGAGAAGAUGAUGACUAUGUUGAUGAUUUUAAUAGUACCAGCCAUCGCUCAGAGAAAAGUGAGAUAAGUAUUGGUGAAGAGAUAGAAGAAGACCUUUCUGUGGAAAUAGAUGACAUCAAUACCAGUGAUAAGCUUGAUGACCUCACACAAGAUCUGACUGUAUCCCAGCUCAGUGAUGUUGCGGAUUAUCUGGAAGAUGUUGCAUAGACACGAAGAAGGAAGUAUUCUAAUUAACAAGGACAGAGGACUGACCGGUUCCAUUUUUUUUUUUUCCAGACAAUCACUCAGCUGGAAUGUCUGCUCUCUAUUGGUGCCUUGCAUUUCAAAAACACUGCAGAUAUUUUUUAAAAGUAAUUUUCAUUUUACUAAACAAAAUACUUCCUAUUUGAGCCCAUGUGUGGAAGAUUUAAUAUUCUUAAUUUAACUGUACAUUUCUUUAUGGAAAUUGAUUAUCUACACUCAGUUUCAUUACAGGGAAGGAACCCAUGAAAACAUCAGUGUUAAGAGCAUGAUGAAAGGUGUCAAUAAAGCCGUAGGAUCGCGCAACCCUUUGUGUGUGUGGCUGCUGGUACGUGUGAUCUUUGAAAACCUUGGCUUUAGCCCUCUGGAAUCAGAGCUUACCCACCAUAGUAUAUUUUGAUAUUAGGUGGUUCUACACAUAGUUGGCAAAAUGACUUGGUAAAUUUGUAAUGCUGAAGUAUAUUAGUAUAAGUUAAAUUUGAUGUGUCAACUUUAUUUUGUAUUUCCUUCCAUUUGGAAGGUUUGUUAGACCAUUAAGGUUAUAUUAAAGUACUCUUGUGUGUGCUAUUUAGUUUUGCUUGUUUUAAAGAAAUCUAGAAGUGGUUAUGAGUUUUAAUUCAUAGAAUUGUCAAUAACAUAACAUUUGCAAUCGUCAUUCCUCCUGUUAUCCAUGUAAGCAGCUUUAGUCGUAGGUUCUCUUCAUUAUAAUUUAUUAUCUGUAAAGAUUCCUUGAAACUUAAAUGCAUCUGAAACCAUUAAGCAGUGCUUUUAUUUCAGAUCUGUAAGUUAAUUGUAUUAAAAUCCAAAUUGGAAUGAAAUAGUAGUAAUGGCCUAAGACCAUGUUCAGUUUGACAAGCUUUAUAUACUGUACAUAAUUUCAUUGUAACCCUUAAAAAUAGAGCCAAUAAUAGAAUUUCCACAGUCUCAUUUAUACGGUUAAAGCAUUAUUGCUAUUAUGUAGGUCACGGAUGUUUAUAAUACUAAAGUAUUUUAAAAUGUGCAAGUAGAAAAAACAGUAGAAAGUGAUGCAUGCAUAUUUAUAUAUAAGUAAAGCAGGAUUGUGCUGUUUUUGCACUUUAUAAUUUCAAUUAAGUUGCGGCUUUUUACUACAAGUUAACUUUAUUAGUAAAAGGAGCAAAUUAGACCUAAUUCAUUGAUCUCGGUUAAGUGAGCAGACUGCAUGACUUGUGUAAUGCCAGUUUCUCAUUUCAUAUUAGCCUAAAUAUUACAGAAAUUACUCCUUGGGCUCUAAAAUGUAGAGGAAAUGAAAAUGUAAGGAUUAAGGCUGUGUAACAGAAUCUGGCUUUUUAAAAUUUAAGUGAAACUAAGCUGUAAACAUCAAGAGGAAGUAGGACAUAAACUGGGCCGGUACAGCCUGGGAGCCCUGUGUAUUUCUGCCCUCCGUCUGUGAGCUGCUAUCUCAGUCUCCUUCAGCUCUUCAUGUCUUAGUAAACAGCACCACGUGCAGAUGUAAUCUUGUUGCAGUCCCCCAGUGUGGUUGUUAUAAAAUGCAUUUCUUUGUAAGUCAUCUCUGUAAACAGUCACUUUCUAAAAGCACUAUAGUUCUGGUCCCCUGGAAUCUGGAUCACAUGUAUGAUUUAUUUUUAAUAUUUGAUAGGAACUAGGUUUCAGUGAAAUGAUUUGAAAGCAUAGCAGGAUGUGGCUUUUUAAAUUUAUGAAACUUUCGAACAGUAGCAACUGAAAUUUGUCACUUUUCUGUUACGCAGAGAAUCAGACCUUUUGAUAAUAUUUGGGAGGGUAAAAGAAAUAUGCCAAAUAUGAAACUUUUUUGUCAGCACUACAUACAUCUUUUUUUUGCGGGGGGCGGGGGGGACAGAGUCUCACUGUGUCACUCAGACUGGAGUACAGUGAUGCGAUCUCGGCUCACUGCAACCUCCGCCUCCUGGGUUCAAGCGAUUCUCCUGCUUCAGCCUCCUGAGUAGCUGGGAUUACAGGUGCACACCACCACGCCCGGCUAAUUUUUGUAUUUUUAGUAGAGAUGGGGUUUCACCAUGUUGGUCAGGCUGGUCUUGAACUCCUGACCUCGUUCCUGCCUUAGCCUCCUAAAGUGCCGGGAUUACAGGCGUGAACCACCGCACCUGGCCAGUACUACAUCCAUUUUAUUGAAUGAUUUUGAAUGACUUAAAGUUCAACUAUGAAAAAGCUUUCUUUUCACAUGUACUUUUUGAUUAGGUAUUAUCAACUUAUGAAACUUGAAGAUGUGAAGUGACAGGUUUUGCAUGUGAUGAGUGUUUUCUGUUAAAAAAUAAAUAUUGAAAUAUUAACCCAUUAAAUACAUUUUUAUGGUAACCUAUGUUUUACAGUGGAGUUUUAAAAAUGCUAGGUCUUUCUUUCAUUUUAUUGAUAACUACAAAUGAAUAAAAAGCAUUUAUUCUCUUUGUUGAUAUUCGGUUGUGCUUUUAUACUUUAUGUUGGAUAACAACCUGUGGGCAGUUGUGUAGAUGCCAUUAGUCCCUGCCUCAUGCUUGCCCACAGCUCUUCCUCCCCUCCUUACUUCCCUCUCCUGCCCAUGCACCAGAGCUGUGCCAGCCCACUGCUGCACAGCCUCUGCACCUGAGCUUGCCAAAGCCCUUCCUGUCUCAAGGUGUGAUAUUUGCCCCUCCUUGUCUGGAAUGUCCUUCCCCUAGAACUGCAUGAAGCUGGUUUAUUUCAGUCUCAUGUUCAAAGACGCUUCCAGACCUAAGGGAGAUGUCCAUUCUCCUCCCUGUCCCUGCCCCACCACUUGCAUUUACCCCUUUUAUUUUAUUCAUCUCAGCAUACUCUGAAAUGGUCUUGCUUAUUUUGUGUGUGUGUGUGUGUGUGUGUGUUUAACUAUGAGCUCGUGAGAACAGGGAUUUUCUUUUAAACUGCUGUGUACCUGGCACAACAUUUGUCCCCUAGUAUGAGCUUGGCAUCUUUGGGGCUGUAAACAGGCUUGAGCACUGACAUGGGGCCUGGAGAAUGUGGUUUCUGGCUAGGCAGCUGGAACAAUCUACAAAAUCUGAGGGGAAAGCUGUCCUUACCCUAAACCUGGGGAGGUCCCUAGGUUCAAGUCUGCAGGAAGGGGAUCUGGUUCAGGAGAAGGCCGUCCUGUGAAUUUGCCCCACCCACCAAGCUCAGCUGGAGCAGGGCCUCUGAAGGAGGUGCCCUCUGUGUGGCUCUGCUGUGGUGUUGGUUCAUGAAGGACAUGGGAGGGGGGCAGGACAGGAGAGGCAGCUCUUCCUGGAGAAAAACACACCCAGCCCAAGUUGGAGCCCUCCUGUGGCAUUGGGUGGGGAGGAUUCCCGCCAUCAGUUCUCUGUCCAUGGGUGCUAGUCUCACCCCUGCCCUCCGAGCAGUCCGUGCUCCCAGUGUCCCUGUCCUCUUUUUUUUUUUUUUUUUUUUUUGAGGUGGAGUUUUGUUCUUGUUGCCCAGGCUGGAGUGCCAUGGGGCGACCUCGGCUCACUGCAACCCCUGCCUUCUGGGUUCAAGUGAUUCUCCUGCCUCAGCCUCCCAAGUAGCUGAGAUUACAGGUGCCUGCCACCAUGCCCAGCUAAUUUUUAUAAUUUUUUUGUAGAGACGGGAUUUCACCAUGUUGGCCAGGCUGGUCUCAAACUCCUGACCUCAGGUGAUCCACCCGCCUCAGCCUCCCAAAGUGCUGGGAAUACAGGUGUGAGUCACGGUGCCCGGCCUAGUCUUCCUGCUCUAGGAAGGGACGUGUUUGGGGAGGAAAUCCAGGGCAGCUACCUUUGUGAGUUGUCCUAAUGCUGCGUUCAGAGUUCCACACGUUCAACAAGCAUCUGACAUUUAAGGAAAGUGAAUGUAUGUCAUGAAAGACAGAUGAACAAAGAACUGAUCUUGAAGAAAAUGUAAUCAGGAAACGAGAUAAUUCAAGAACAAAAACCUGUGAAGGACUGAAUGUGUCCCCCAAAAUGUGUAUGUCGAAACCUAAUCCCACAUAGGAUGGAAUUAGGUAGGGCCUCUGGAAGUUGAUGAGAUCAUUAGCGCCCUUAUAGGAGGCCCGGGAGAGCUGCUUUGCCCCUUCCAGCGUGUGAGGACACAGUGAGGAGGUGUUGCCUAUGAGGAAACAGGCCCUCCCAGAUGGUGAACCUGCCGGUACCUUGAUCUUGGACUUAAGCCAUCUGAGCUGUGAGCCCUACACUUCCAUUCUUUAUAAAUUAUCCAGUCCAAGGUACUUUAGGAACCUGAAUGGAUUAAGACAAACCUGAUUAUGCCACUCCGAGAUUUGAGGUAACAUUUGAAUCUAAAAGAGGCUAUAUGAAAGAGGUUAUAAUAAAAAUGAUUUUUGACUAAAAAAUUGUUGGCCUAAGAUAAUUCAGUAGCAGGGCUGAAUAAUGGGAUGACUCAAAAUCAGUAAGCUCAAAGGCAAUUUCAAAGAAAUCUUUAUGUUUAGCAAGAAGACCAAGAUGACAAGAUGCGCCAGGAGACUUGGCCAGAGGACCUCCAGGCUGACAAAGUUUCCCCGAGGAAGUCAGAUUGGAAAAGUGUCCUCAGGUUCAAGGAAACCUGGGUGUGCACCGGGUGAAUGAGAGUGGCAGACAGAAGGAAACAGCAAGGCCUCUGAGGUAGGAGGGACAGCGUUUUUGAAUGUGAAAUUUAUUCCCUGAUACAUGUUUUUAAAAAUGAAUCUUGCUGCCCUUAGAAAAUGAACCCCCGAACAAGGUAAGGUCGAGCUGGCCCCUCGUGUCAUCCGACUUUGCGUUGUGGCCCUGCCUGCAGAAACGUGUGCUCUGCUACAGCCCUGGGAGGAGGGGCCGGGCUCCCAACUCCUGCCCCGCUUCUAGCACAUGCUGUGCUUGGCCACUUCUCUGCCUCUUAGUUUAACAGCAGCACUGGGCAAGGUUUGCCCUCUGCACACCAGACCGGCUUCCCAAGAACCGGGGAAGAGGAGAGGGCAUGCCUGGGGCCUGAGCUUAGUGGGCCGGGUGGAGGCAGGAGGUACUGCAUGGAGGAGCGUGGACAGUGGCAUGCAGGAGGCCAGUCAUUCUGCGGUUUUAGCUGGAGGUUUGUUUUUGGUAGUUUGUAGAAUCAUCAGAUUUGAUGAUGAAACUUUUUUUCCAUAAAUGUUAAAUUUUCAGACACUUGUAUUUUUUUUUUCCUUUUUUUUUUUUGAGACUGAGUCACUGUCGCCCAGGCUGGAGUGCAGUGGUACUAGCUCGGCUCACUGCAACCUCUGCCUCCCAGGUUCAAGCGAUUCUCCUGCCUCAGCCUCCUGAGUAGCUGGGAUUACAGAUGUGUUUCACCAUGCCCGGCGAAUUUUUUUUGUAUUUUUAGUAGACACGGGAUCUCACCGUGUUGGCCAGGCUGGUCUUGAACUCCUGACCUAUGGUGAUCCGCACCCCUCCCCGCCCCCCCCGCGGCCCAGCCUCCCAAAGUGCUGGGAUUACAGGCAUGAGCCACUGUACCCAGCCCUGUAUUUUCUUUAAAAACCAAUUUUGGGCCGGGCACGGUGGCUCACGCCUGUAAUCCCAGCACUUUGGGAGGCCGAGGCAGGCGGAUCACGAGGUCAGGAGAUCGAGACCAUCCUGGCUAACAUGGUGAAAACCCAUCUCUACUAAAAAUACAGAAAAAAAAUGAGCUGGGUGCGAUGGUGGGUGCCUGCAGUCCCAGCUACUCGGGAGGCUGAGGCAGGAGAAUGGCGUGAACCCAGGAGGCGGAGCUUGCAGUGAGCCCAGAUCACGCCCCUGCACUCCAGCCUGGGUGACAGAGCGAGACUCCGUCUCAAAAACAACAACAACAACGAAAAAACGAUUUUGGCAUGUUUUGUAAGUUGCCAGACUAUUGGAUAUACCUCUUAAUCAUACUUUGUUUGAAAUCCUUUGUGGUUUCUAAAGCACUAGUAGCUUUCUGAAAGGAAAAUUUUUAAUGAAUGAAGCAUGCUUCAUCCUGCACAUCCCCUCCUGCCCCAGCACCCCUACUGCCCAUGCGCCUCUCCUGCCCCAGCACCCCUACUGCCCCAGUGCCAGGCCUUUUCUAGCAGCUCUCAUGGGUUCAUCCCUGCUGCGGGCAUUGCUCCACCAAGGGGCAGUGCUCUCCCUGCCGGUAAGUGUUGGAACUUCACGUUUCCCUCUAGUUUUCUCUUUACAUUUUAACAUACACUAUUAUGUGUCAAUAUAUUAAUUAUAUAUUAAUUACAUUUAUAGAGGUUAGGUAUAUAUGGCAGAUCAUAUCUGAGCGUGAAUUACAUUCUCCAAUAUUUUUAUUUGUCAUGAUUUAUUGCAGGGUUCACUUAUUUGAUCUACCCCAACUUAACACACAUUUCCAAGAAAAUAUCCAUCACACUAGAAAGAAAGAAAGAGGAAGGAAGGAAGGGAGGGAGGGAGAGAAGGAGAAAGGAAGAAAGGGAAGGAAAAUGGAAUGGAGGAAGGGAAAAAUGGAAGGAGGAAGGAAGGAAGGGAAAGAAUGAAGAAAGCCAUUUGUUCCUGCAAACCUAAACCUCUUUGUAGUAAGUUCUGGCAGAAGGUGUGUUUCUGGAGUUAAACUACAGGCUUGGAAAUGGAAUUUCUUAGCCUAAUUUCUAAAUUAGAACUGCUUAUGCAAAUUAACACUCCGUACAUUUCAACAAGCAGUUGGCUGAUUUCUUCUGUCCACUCCACCUGCAGAUGCAGAGGUGGCCCCAUCCUGUGAUGUGCCACCACAUCCCUUUUCAGUGAAGGGCUUUGUUGGCUGCUGUGGGCAUUCUCAUGGCCUCUCCAGGGAUGGCCUCCACUGUAGAGACCUAUGUCACCAAGGCCAGGCCCUCUCAGGGGGCUCCAUCCAACGACCAUUCUGCCUCAGGGUAAGAGGCCCGGCCCUCUCAGCCUGAGUCCAUUCUGGCUCCAGAGCUCCCUGAGAGCUUGCCUGGCAAGUUACUCUUGCAAUUCUAGCUUCCAGCAGGCGUUGAUUUCUGGGGCACUUUUGAUAAACUCCUGGCAGGAAACUCAAUCUCUGGGGGUCAGAGUCCACUUCCUGGGGAGCCCAAUCUGUGACCCCUAGGAGUGGGGACCAUGGAAGCACUUGGCUCUCCAGCAUGUGCUGAAUAGGGGGCGCUGCCUGCAAUGUCCACGUGGAAACCUGGCUGGGAGAAUGCCUGUGUGCUCUGCAUGGGGAUGUAAAGGUGUGAGCAAACCUUCUUCAGAGAGGGGAUGUUCAAUGCGAAAUUUGAACAUUGGGACCUGAAAAACUGAUGGGCUGAUGGGGUCUGCCCAUGAUUGGCAGCCUUCAUAGAAUCACGAGGGAGGAGCACAGGCCACCCUAGACAGGAGGGGUCCCCUACUGACAGGGAGGUGCUGUCGGGGCAGCAGGCACGUGCAGGAAAACGGAAAAGCAGAGUAAUUGAAUGUAAAUCAUGCAACUCCACUACAGUGGCUAGAAGCCUGGAUGGGCAACUUGGCUGAGUGAUGUUGGGCAAGUUAUUUAAUAUCAGUAUUCUCAGUUUUCUCAUCUGUAAAGGGGAUUAAAUACUUCCUUCCCUUACAGGGCUGCCCUGGUCUUAAGUAAUGCCCACAGAGAGCUUAGCAUUGUUCUUGGCAAGUCACUAGUACUCAGUAAAUACUAUUUUUAUUAAGAAGGUAAGAUUCACAGGACUUAGUGUCUUAACUAGAUGUUGAGAGUAAGGAGAAGAGAGAAUACUUCUCGGAUGAUUGUUCAGUUUCUGAUGAAUGUCUGUUCCCCUUUCAAAACCUAAUUCAGAUGUCACUUCCUCCUCAAAGCUCUCGCCCCGCGCCGAGCUACUGUGAUGUAUUUUUAUGACCUGGCAGCUUUUUUCUCAUAUCCCUGUUAGCGGUAUGUGGUAAGAACAUGAGACACAGAAUCAGAAACCAUGGAUUUCUGGUCUUGACUCCACUACCACUCAGAGGAACCUCACGGUGGAUGCCGUAAGUGUUUACACUGAAAAGGAUUUUCACGAAAACCUGCAUUUUCAUUUCGUUCACAAGAGAAUUAUGAGACUAGAAAAACAACAAUUCUUAGUAUACCACAGACUGUGGUGCCUAGGAAUAACAGACAAGCUUUAACUCACACGAUGAGCAUCUUUAUUUAGCUCUGCUUUUAGAUAUCUGCAUGAUAAAGAUGAGUGAUCCAACGUUAGAAAUCAUCUGGACAUUAAAACUGAAUUGUAGGCAGGCGUGGUGGCUCACACCUGUAAUCCCAGCACUUACGGAGACCAAGGCGGGCAGAUUGCUUGAGCUCAGGAGUUUGUGAGACUAGCCUGGGCAACAUAGUAAGACCCCUAUCUCUACAAAAAAUAUAAAAAUUAGCUAGGCAUCAUGGCCUGUGCCUGUAGUCCUAGCUAUUGAGGAAACUGAUGCAGGAGGAUCAUUUGAGCUCAGGAGUUUGAGACCAUUCUGGGCAAUACGGUGAAACCCUGUCUCUACAAAAAAAUGCAAAGAUUAGCUAGGCAUGAUGGCACAUGCCUGUGGUCCCAGCUACUCGGGAGGCUGAGGCAGGAGGAUUGCAGGAGGUUUGCUUGAGCCGGGGAGGUCGAGUCUGCAGUGAACUGAGAUUGCAUCACUGCACUACAGCCUGGGUGACAGAGUAAGACCCUAUCUCAAAAAAAAGAACUAAUUGUAACAAACUAUCUUUCAAAUUAUAUCAAAACAGUGAUUCAUAAAUUCCAUGUUGCCCAGAGAUCAUGAGGAGCUCUUCUAUGAUUUGACAGUGCAAUUACUGAAGGGGAAGACACCAUGCAAAUACAUGGUAAAAAUAUUCAAAUUAUUACUGAUUUGACACAAAAUAUUGAUGUAAAUAACAUAAAACUGUAAUAUGCCAUUAUGAUGACAUUAAUGAAAAAUUGGUUAAUGAAUGUCAUUGAAAGAGCAUGUACAUCACUAAAUGUUCUUAGUCACUGAAAGUGUGAAAUAGCCUCUAAACUCAUAUGUGGAAAAAGAACUUGAAAAAGGUUUCCAGAAAUGUGACAAUUCUAGUACUUUCAUGACAUUUUAAAAAAGGGAUUGUAAAGACUGAUGAAACCCUUAAAACCUCUCAAGAAUUAAAAAUCAUUUUUGAUCAACAGAGUAAACUGAUUUUUUAUCUCUGUUGAAAGAUAUUUUUAAAAUCAUUGUCCUAUGGAAAAGUCAUAUAGAACGUUUGCUGUUUAAUGUAGCACAGAUGUAUCAAAAAGCCAUGCCAGGCAGUUAUAGAUAUCUUAGUUUUCUGGAUUUUGUGACGUUUGUGGUAUUUGUCAGAUUUUUAAAAUUUGUGAUUUGUUGGGAUUUGUUCCUCAUUCACAGGUAAUUUUAUAUACUUUUGUAUUCACUUUCGAAAAGAAGGCAACUCUAAAUUUUAUGAACUUCAAGUGCUAUAAAACAAUUACCACAGUAAAUUUUGAAAAAUUCACCCCAAAAAGAAACCUUGUAUCCAUUGGCAGUAACUCCCUAUGCUCCGCCAUUCCUCUCAGCUCCCUGUCUGGCAACCACUUCCUGUCUCUUCAGAGUUGCCUCUUCUGGACAUUACAUAUAAACGGAAUUAUACACUAUGUGGCCUUUUAUGACUGGCUUCUUUCACUUAGCAUAAUGUUUUCAAGAGUCAUCUGUGUUGUAGCAUUUGUCAGUACUUCAUUUAUUUUUGUUUCCUAACAAUACUCCAUUGUAGGGAUUGACCACACUUUAUCCAUUCAUUGGUUGAUGGACAUUUGGGUUGUUUCCACUUUUUCUGCUGUUGUGAAUAACAGUGCUAAGCACAUUCAUAUGCAGUGUUUGUGUAGAUAUAUAAUAUGCUUUAUUUUCUCUUGAGUACAUAAAAGUGGAGCCUCUGAGUAAUAUAAUAACUCUAUGUUUGGUGUUUUGAAGAAUUGCUAAAUUGUUUUCCAAAGCAGCUGCACCAUUUUAUAUCCCUACCAGCAAUGCAUGAAGCUUCCAGUUUCUCCACAUCAUCACGAAUACUCCUUAUUCUCUCUCUUUUUAGAUAUAGACAUUCUGGCAGGUGUGACAUUGUAUCUCUUGUGGUUUAGAUUUGCAUUUGGAGCAUGUCUUAUGUGCACUUAAAAAUAUUAAUAUCUAUUCUGCUGUUGUUGGGUAAACUGUUCUAUAGAUGUUGAUAUGGCUUCGCUGUGUCCCCACUCAAAAUCUCAUCUUGACUUGUAAUCCCCAUAAUCUCCAUGUGUCAAGGGUGGGACCAGGUGGAGGUAAUUGGAUCAUGAGGGUGGUUUUCCCUACUCUGUUUUCAUGAUAGUGAGUCUCACAAGGUCUGAUGGUUUUAUAAGCAUCUGGCAUUUCCCCUGCUUGCACUCAGGCUGUCCUGCCACACUGUGAAGAAGGUGCCUUGCUUCUCCUUUGCCUUCUGCCAUGAGUGUAAGUUUCAUGAGGCCUCCCCAGCCAUGCUGAACUGUGAGUCAAUUAAACCUCUUUCCUUUAUAAAUUACCAAGCUGCGGCUAUUUCUUCAUAGCAGUGUGAGAACGGACUAAUACAGGUGUUUUUUAGGUCUUGUUAUUGUGUCGUUCACGUCUUUUAUUUCCUUGUUGAUCUUACUCUUAGUUGUUCUAUCCAUCAUUGAAAAUGGGGCAUUGGCCAGGCGUGGUGGCUCACGCCUGUAAUCCCAGCACUUUGGGAGGCCAAGACCAGCAGAUCACUUGAGGUCAGGGGUUCGAGACCAGCGUGGCUAACAUGGAGAACUCCUGUCUCUACUAAAAAUACAAAAAUUAGUCAGGUGUGGCAGUGCGUGCCCGCCUAUAGUCCCAUCUACUUGGGAGGCUGAGGCAGGGGAAUUGCUUGAACCCUGGAGUCAGAGUUUGCAGUGAGCUGAGAUCAUGCCACUGCGCUCCAGUCUGGGUGACAGAGUGAGACUCAAAAAAGAAAAAAAAAAAAAAAAAAAAAAAGAAAGAAAAUGAGACAUUGGAUUUGUAAGUUUCUGACAGGUUCAUUUUGCCUGCUGCCCAGAUAGAGCCGAUUUAUGAGGACAGGGAAAUUGCAAUAGAGAAAGAGUUUAAUACAUGUAGAACUGGCUAAACAAGAGACUGGAGUUUUAUUAUUACUCAAAUCAGCCUCCACAAAAAUUUGGAGGCUAGGUCUUUUCAAAGAUAGUUUGGUGGGCAGGGGUUUGUGUACUAAGAAACUAAAUGUUUCUUGUGUACUAAGUCAGCUUCUGGGUGGGGGCCAGAGGACCAGUUGAGCCAAGAAUUCAAGAGGUACAGGUUCAAGUAGGGCCAUCUGGUUGUCAGAAAUGCAAAAGCCUGGAAAGUCAUCUCAAAUGUUAGGUUCUACAAUAGUCAAGUUAUUUAUAGUAAUUGGGAAAGUUGCAAAUCUUGUGACCUCUGUAGAAAAUAGGUGGUAAUCUUUACACCUAUAUCUUAGUAGAAUUCAGGCCCCUCACUUCCUCCUAACCUGGUAGCCUUUCAUUAGUUUUACAAAGGCAGUUUAAUUUUGGGGGGCAGGGCUAUUAUCAUCUAAACUAUAAACUAUAAUCGUUUGUCCCAAAGUUAGCUUGGCCCAUGCCCAGGAAUGACCAAGGGCAAUUUGGAGAUUAAAGUCAAGAUGGAGUUGGUUAGAUCAGAUCUCUUUCACUGUUAUAAUUUUCUCACUGUUAAAAUUUACAAAGGCAGUUUCAAAAUCUGAAACUUUUAUUGUUAAAUUAUGUAUUUAUUCCUUUAGUUCUGUCAUGUUCUGCUUCUUAUAUUUUGGAACUCUGUUGUUAGGUGCAUACAUAUUUAUAAUUGUUAUAUCUUCCUGAUGGAUUGGUAUUGUAAUCACUGUAAAAUACACUAUUAUCAUUGUAAAAUAUUCCUUUUUAUCUCUAGUAUUUUUUGUCUGUUUGACUUAAAGUCUAUUUUGUUUGAUAUUAGCAUAGCUAUUCUUGCUCUUACUGUGGCAAUUUGUAUGAUACCUUUUUCUUUUAGCCUAUUUAUAUCUUUGAAUCAAAAGUUUGUCUCCUGUAGAUAGCAUAUAGUUGGAUAAUUUUUAGUUCUUUUGAUUGGAUUGUUUAAUUCAUUCAUUUUUAGUGUUACUAUUGAUAUGGCUGGAUUUGUGUCUGCAAUUUUAAUUUUUGUUUUCUAUAUGUCUCGUGUUUUUGUGGCUUUGCUUCUUCUUCUUUGCUUUCUUUUGCAUUAAGUAUUUUCUAGUUUAACAACUUAAUUUCUUAAAUUAUUUUUAACUAUAUUUUUACGUAUUUCCUUAAUGAAUGCUUGAUGGCUCACAAUCUCCUUCUCAGUUUAUCAGAAUCUACUUAAGUUUAUACUAACUUAUGUCCAGUGAGAUAGAAACACAUUUCUUCUUUAUAGCUCUAGGUCCUCUUCACUUGUUUUUGUGCUAUUAUUGUUAUACUUACUACCUCUGUAUAUGUUACAAGCCCAAGAAUACUAUUCUACUUAUUUAUAUAAUUUUAUGUUUUUUAAAGAACCUGAGACUGGAAGUGAGGGAAAUAGGGCGUGCAGGAAGGAAGGAAGAGGAAGGAAAAGUGUGUGAAAGGGGGCUCCACCUCCUUUAGUGGAUACCCUGAGCUUAUUUCCAGGGGCCUUUGUAAAUUCCCAGUGACAACUCUUUGGAAGAUGAAAUCCCCCUCUUCCCUGCAUCUUAUUAGAACAGUGUAUCCUGGAGGACAUCCCUUGCCUUUCACCAAGUGACCCUAUACUGGCGGCAGAACUUCUCGAUUUUGCGGAUUUCAAAAUGGCUCCACGUACUCAUAGUUUUCAUGACAGACUUCAUUGCGAUAGUCAAAUACUGUUCCACUUACUGCAGUUGCCUACAGUCUGGGUUUUGUUCAGUUGAAAUUAAAUAAAUUUUAUGCACAAACCUUU